CAAUGAGAAAACUGAGGCUUAAGGAGGUGUAAAAAAUACUUUCUUUUAAAAAAAAUACACCUCUCCCCCACCAUCAUAAAAACCCCAACUUUGGCCAUAGAGUUCAUUGGUGGUGGAGCACUGCAAACAUUAGCUGUCCCAUGUGGCUUUGACUCUGACACAAUUGGUCCUCUUGCUUCAGGGAACUGGAUACCAUCCAUCCCUCCCAUGGGUUGGCCUAGGCUCUGUUACUUCAGAGUUUUCUUGACGAGUUUCAAGGUAACCAGGUCAUCCUGUUCUACAUAUUUUUCUGGGAUUGAGGUCAAGGAGCAGCAUGAUCCUCUCUUAAAUGGGUCAGAGGAGGAGGACUCCUGUGGCUCCCUGAAAGGUCAAGCCCCUUCAUGCUAACUACACCGUCUUCCCUUCUCUUCCAGCUUAUGUCCUGGGCUGGGCUCUGGACAGGGAGCAGAGGCAGAUGUGCGCAUGUGUUCUGGAGGACUUUUAUAUGUCCGAUGGUGUGUUAGGCACUAUGUGGAGUGGAGGCAGAGGGAACUCCAGAAAAGAUAAAUUAUCUUAUGGUGGAGACAAAAGGUAGUAUUGGCAACAAACAUGACCUCUGGAAUCAGAUAGUUUUGGGUUCCAGGCCUGACUCUUUGACUCACUUAUUAGUUGUGCGACCUUAGGCAAUUUAUUUAACCUUUCUGUAGCUCAGUUUCCUUGUAUGCAAACAGGAGGAAAAUAAUAAUCUCUUACAUAAUAGGAUUGCUAUGAAGAAUAUAUGAACUAAUAUGUGUAAGACAUUGACUGUAGUGCCAGGCACCUAGUAAGCACUCAGUAAGGAAUAACUACUGCCAUUAUUGUUGUUACUAACAACAGUAUGAGACUAAUAAGUGAUUAGUGUAUAAGUACCAACAAAUACCAAUGGAGUUCAGAAAAAGAAUGCUUAAUUUUUGUGACUUAUCCAGGAAAUCUCUAGAGGAGACAGAAGAAGUGGAAUGAAAUAUUCCAGGUGGAGCAAAUAUGAAAGUGGGAGGCUGAACUGAACUGGAGUGGGGAACAAAAAGAAGAAACAAACGCAACAUCUGGCACCCUUGAGCUCUACCACCAGCUCACCUGUUGUCACUACCAAUAUGUCCAGUCCUUUAUGGCUCUCCAUUUUGGAGUGCCCUGAAUUACUGGCUGCAGUUUUGACUUGGCCAGCUAGUUGGCCAGCUGCUCUGACUGAGCUUGAGGGUGUCUGUGCCUUGGUGGAGUUGACACGGGUCCUAACUCUGCAACUUGGUUUGUAGGUUCAAAGCCUAAUUUUUAUCAGCUUACCCAGGGCUGUUGGUUUCUAGUGGAUUGGGUCACACUCCCCAACAUUACAAAACACUUCUUAAUAAAUCACCAGGCUGAUAAGUCGAUUGAUGAUGAGAGAGAGACCUUUAUAGAGAUGAGAACACUUGUGUGUAUCAGCCCUUUCUGAUAUCAAGGUACCUGAAGCCAAAUUAAACAGGGACUGUUUUAUAACCUAAAAUCAGAACCUAAUGGAGUUGAAAAGUCUCAUGAGCGAGACCAUAUAGGCUUUGGUAGUCCAUGGAAAACUGUACCUUUUUGCAUGUCUGUCAUAGCUUUGUAGUGUGACCAGAAUGUGUGUCCUGUUCUCUCUCCACUGCUGGAGAAACAUCAGUAACAAUUUUUCUCUUGGAUGUUCCUGUUUUCAAUUCCAUGCAAAUGCUGUUUGUGUGCUAUGGCCAUGCUAUUCUCUUGAAUUUCUUUUUUCUUGACAAGAUUUUUGAGUUGCCUACUUCUCAGCGACAACAUAGUGAUUCUCUCAUUGAGUGUUCUUUUUGGCUUUGUUCUCAAACACUAGGAAUGUUUCCAAGCAGGGCCGCCACGAAUGGCUAUGCACUGCACAACCCUAGGAGAGGGUGCCAUUCACAUAGACUAUAAUUGAAUGGCGCCACUAGGGUUGUGCAGUGCACAACCUACACAACUGUACUCGGCGGCCCUGGCAUAAUGUAAUGUCAGUACUUUCUUCAUCAAGGUACCAGUUUGGGAUUGUCCUCAGGGUAAGGGGGCUGAAGCAGUGAGCUGCUGCUGUGACCAGGAAAGGAAGAAAGAAGUAAAGUUGUGGCUUUGGGAGAAUUAUCUUCUCUGUAAAUGAGAGCCAUCAUAUAGGAGAACUACGUACCUUCGUUCUUUCAGUAAAUAGUUUUUUAAGUGCCUACUAUGUGAGGGUUGAAGAACAGGGAGGGGUUUGCAUAGGAGGGAGCAUUUGAACUGGGCUUUGUGAAAGAAGUAGAAUAUUAACAUGUGAAGAUGAGUCAGGAGGAGAGAAUCUCAGGGGGAAGGAAUAGCGAGAAGAAAGACAGAUGGGAGACCACAAGGGAUAUAUGGGUAAUGGUGCAUAAUUCAUCUUGGUUGGAUAGAAAAGCAUGUAAAAGGGAGUAGUGAGCAAUGAUGCUGGUCGGGGGUCAAAUGAUGAUGCAGGAGGGGAGGGAGUUGAAUGCCCAAUUAAGGAAUUUGGACUUUUAUUUAUCAAGCAAUAAGGAGCUAUCCAAAGUUUGUUUUUUAAACAGCUUUAUUGGGUUAUAAUCAUAUACCAUAUAAUUCAUUCAUUUAAAGUGUACAAUUGAAUGUUUUUAGUAUAUUCACAUAUAUGUGCAACCACCACCACAGUCAAAUUUAGAACAUUUUCAUCAUCCAAAAAAUAACUCCAUACGAUUUAGCUCACCCCCCUCCCUACCUUUCCCCCACUCACCAGCCCUAAGCAAUUGUUAAUCUACUUUCUGUUUCUAUAGAUUUUAUCUAUUCUGGACAUUUCAUAGAAAUUGAGUAAUUAUAAUAUGUGACCUUUUUCCACUGGCUUCUUUCACUUAGUAUGUUUUCGAGAUUCAUCUGUGUUUAGCAUGUAUCAGUACUUCACUUAUUUUUAUGGCCAAUUAAUAUUCCAUUUUAAGGAUAUGCCACAUUUUAUGUAUCCAUUUGUCUGUUGGUGAGCAUUUGGGUUGUUUCUGCCUUUUGGCUAUUACAGAUAAUACUUCUGUGAACAUCUGUAAGUUUUCAGGUGCACAUAGGUUUUUAUUUCCCUUGGACAUAGGUUUUCAUUUCCCCCAGGUAUAGGAGUGGAAUUGCUGAGUCAUAUGAUAACUCUAUGUUUAACCUCUCAAGGAGCUGCCAGACUGUUUCUCUAAAAUGGCAGCAUCAUUUUACAUCCCUACCGACAGUAUAAAAGGGUUCCAAUUUCUCCACAUCCUCAUGCACACUUGUGUUUGCCUUUUAUAUUUUGGCCAUGCUAGUGGGUAUGAAGUGUCAUCUCAUUGUGGAUUUGAUUUGCAUUUCCCUGAUGACUAAUGAUGUUGAACAUCUUUUCAUGUGCAUGUUGAGUACCCGUGUGUUUUCUUUGGAGAGAUGUCUGUUCAAGGUUAUUUAUCUUUUUAUUGUUGAGUUUUUUUAAUACUUUAGCUAUUUUUAAUGUAUAUAUUUAAGGUUUUCAACUUAAUGAUUAUAUAUAUAUAUGGAAAUCACCACAAUCAAGAUAACACAUGCAUUACAUCAUAGAGUUAUCAUUUAUGUGUGUAUGCGUGUGUGUGUGUGUUGGAAAUACUUAGGAUCUAUUCUUAUAGCAAAUUUUAAGUAUACAGUACAGUAUUUUCACCUAUAGUCGCCAUGCUGUACAUUAGAUAUCCAGGACUUACUUGUCCUGGAAAACUAAAACUUUGUACUUUUUGACUAACAUCUUACUUUCCCAGCACCAGCCCCAGCUAACCAUCAUUUUAUACUCAGCUUCUAUGAGUUAGACUAAUUUACAUUUCAUAUUUAUGUGACAUCAUAAGAUAUUUUUCUUUCUGGCUCAUUUCACUUAACAUAAUGUCCUUUGGGUCCUUCUGUGUUACUGCAAAUGAUAGGAUAUCCUUCUUUUUAAAGGCUGGAUAAUAUACCACAUUUUCUUUAUUCAUGCAUCCAUCGAUGAACAUUUAUCUUGUUUCUAUAUCUUUGCUAUUGUGAAUAACGGUGCAAGGAAUAUAGGAGUGCAGAUAUCCCUUUGAGAUCUUGAUUUCAACUGUUGGAUAAGUAUUCCAGAAGUGGGAUUGCUGUGUCAUAGAAUAGGUCUUUUUUUUUUUUUUUUUUUGAAACUAUACUAUUUUUGAUAAUGGCUCUAUUGAUCUCCAUCAGCAGUUUUCCAGGGUUCUGUUUUCUCCACACCCUUCCCAAUAUUGCCAUCUUUUGCAUUUUUUAUAAUAGCCAUUCUGACAAGGGUGACAUGAGAUCUCACUGUGGUUUUCAUUUGCAUAUCCCCAAUGAUUAGUGAUGUUGAGCACCUUUUCAUAUACCUGUUGUCCAUUUGUAUGCCUUCUUUGGAAAAAUGUCUAUUCAGAUCCUUUGCCCAUUUUAAAAUUGGGUUAUUUGUAUUUCUGCUAUUGAGUUUAUGAGUUCUUUACAUAUUUUAAAUAUUGACAUCAAAUUUGUGGUUUGCAAAUAUUUGCUAUAUAGCUUUUUAGGUUGAUGUAGUCCUAAUUGUUUUUGUUUGUUUGUUUUUUACUUUUCUUGCACGUGCUUUUGAUGUCAUAUUCAAAAAAUCAUUGCCAAGACCAAUUUCAAGAAGUUUUUCCUAUGUUUUCUUCUAGGAGUUUUAUGGUUUCAGAUGUUACAUUUAAGUCUUAAGCCCAUUUUGAGUUGGUUUUUGUGUGUGGUGUAAGAUAAGAGUCUGAUUUCAUUACUUUGCGUGUGGAUAUCCAGUUACCCCAACAUCAUUUGUUCAAGCAAGCAUCUUUUCCCCCAUUGUGUAUUUUUGACCCUCUAAGGUUCUUUAUUCCUUUUCAUCCUUUUUUUUCUUUUUCUCUUCUGAUGAGGUAAUUUUAAAUAACUGUUCUUCAAAUUUGCUGGUUCUUUCUUCUGCUUGAUAAAUCUCCUGUUUUUAGUUGAGUCAUUGUAUUCCUCAGCUCCAGAAUUUGUUUGGCUGUUGUUUACAGUUUCUAUCUUUUUAUUUAACUUUUCAUUUUGAUCAUACAUUGUUUUCCUGAUUUCAUUGAGUUGUCCAUCUGUUAAUUUUCUUUUUUAUUGUUGAGUCUUAAGAGCUAUUUAUUCUGAAUACUAGACUCCUAUUAGAUACAUGAUUUGCAGAUUUUUUCUCCCAUUCUUUGGGUCCCCUCCCCUCCCCUCCCCUUUCUUUCUUUUUUUUUUUUUUGAGACAGAGUCUCACUCUGAUGCCCAGGCUGGAGUGUGCAGUGGUGUGAUCUCAGCUCACUGCAACCUCUGCCUCCCUGGUUCAAGCACUUCUCCUGCCUCAGCAGGAGAAGUAAUCCCAAGUAGCUGGGAUUACAGGCAUGUGAUGUGCCACAACGCCUGGCUAAUUUUUUUUUUUUUUAAUUUUUAGUAGAGACAGAGUUUUGCUGUGUGGGCCAGGCUGGUCUCAAACUCCUGACCUCAAGUGAUCUGCCUGCCUCGGCCUCCCAAAGUGCUGGGAUUACAGGUGUGAGCCACCAUGCUCAGUCUGGGAUGUCUUUUCACUUUCUUAAUAGUGUCAUUUGAAGCAUGAAAUAUUUUAAUUUUGGUGAAGUACAGUAUAUUUAUUUUUUCUUUUGUUGCUUGUGCUUUUGGUUACAUCUUAGAGUCUGUUACCAAAUCCUAGGUCAUGACAUGUAUCCCUAUGCUUUCUUUUACAAGUUUUAUAGUUUUUGCUCUUACAGUUAGGUCUUUGAUUUUGAGUGAAUUUUUGUAUAUGGGUUAUGAGGUAGGGGUCCAACUUAAUUCUUUUGCCUGUGGAUAACCAGUUGUCCCAGCAUCAUUUGUUGAAGAGACUGUUCUUUCUACCAUUGGAUGGUCUUGAUACCUUAGUCAAAAAUCACUUCUGAGGAUUUAUUUCAGUACUCUCAAUUCUAUUCUGUUGGUCUCUGUGUCUUUCCUUAGGUUAGUACCACACUGUCUUUGUUACUGUUGCUUUGCCAUAAGUUGAAAUCAGGCUGUGUAAGUCCUCCCACUUUUUCUUUUCAAGGUUGGUUUGGCUGUUUGGGGUCCCUUGCAUUUCCAUAUGAAUUUUAAAAUCAGCGUGUCAGUUUCUACAAAAAAAAAUGUCAGCUGGGAUUCUGAUACGUACUGUGAUGAAUCUGUCAUUUAAAACUUUCAAGGAGGAGUGUAACAGGAUCAGAAUGCUAUUUUAAGAAUAGGAACCUGACAAUACUAUAUAAAAUUAGAGCAAGCUUGUCCAGCCUGUGGACUGCAUGUAGCCCAAGACAGCUUUGAAUGCAGCCCAACACAAAUUCAUAAAUUUUCUUAAAACAUUAUGAGAUUUUUUUGCAAUUAUUUUAAAAAGAUCAUCAGCUAUCAUUAGUGUUAGUGUAUUUUAUGUGUAGACCGAGACAAUUCUUCUUCCAGUGUGGCUCAGGGAAGCCAAAAGAUUGGACACCCGUGAAUUAGAGUGAUGAAGGAAAAACACUGGAUACUUGGAGAUCAGAUAGGAAACUGCUGUAGUAGUUUAAGAAAAUGAUAGGGACCAAACUAGGAAAAGAUAGUGAGGGUGGAUUUCAGAUGUAUUGAAAAGGUUGGGCUGGGUGCAGUGGCUCACACUAGUAAUCUUAGUGCUUUGGGAGGCUGAGGUGGGAGGAUCACUUGAAGCCAGGAGCUUGAGACCAAUCUGGGUAACAAAAUGAGACCCCAUAUGUACAAAAAAUAAAAAAUAAAAAUAGCUAGGUGUGGUGGCACAUGCCUGUAGUCCUAACUACUCAGGAGGCUGAGGUGAGAGGAUUGCUUGAGCCUAGGAGUUUGAGGCUGCAGUGAGCCAUGAUCACACCAAUGCACUCCAGACUGGGUGACAAACCAAGACCCUGUCUGAAAAAAAAAAAAAAAAAAGAAAAGAAAAAGAAAAGGUCUAAGUGACAAGACAGGAUUUGGGGACUGAAUACAUGUGGGGCUGAGAAAGGUGGGGGAUCAGGGGUAACUCUGAGGUGUGAAGAGAGGCUAAUGGAUUAGAUUAUAGUACCUUUUAAAACUUUGUAUUAUUUUGAAAUGACUUUUGACUUACAGAAGAGUUGUAAAGAUAUUACAGAGAAUUCCUGUAUAUCCUUCACCCAGCUUCCCCUAAUGUUAACAUUUUACAUAACUAUGGUAAAAUUAUUAAAACUGAAAAAUUAGCAUUUAUACAAUGCAAUAUGAACUUAACUACAGUCUUUAUUUGGGUUUUACCAGUUUUUUUCACAAAUGUCCCUUUUCUGUUGCAGGAUCUAUUUAGGAUCCUUAAUUGCAUUUAGAUAUGAUCUCUCUUUAGUCUUCUCUAAUCUGUGGUAGUUCCUUAGUCUUUGCCUUUCACAACCUUGACUAUUUUGAAGAGUACUGUUCAGUUUACUCUGUAGAAUGCCCCUGAUUUGGGUUUAUCUGAUGUUUUUUCAUGAUUCCAUUGAGAUUAUACAAUUUGGGCAUCCAAUAAGGACGAUGCUAUCAAUAGCUCAUACUUAUUUUAUUCCCUACAGUGUGCCAGGCAUUUGAACUAGGUACCUCAAGCAUUUAAAUUUUACAGUUACCCUAUGAAAUAAUACUAUUGUAAUCCUCACUUGACAGAUAAGGGAACUGAGCCUAAAGGGUUAAGUAUUCUCUGUAGGCAGCUGGACAAGGGAAGUUGAGUAAUAUGUCAGAAUGUUGUUAUUGCAAACAUGGAAUUAAAACAAGUGAAGUUAGAGGAAUUGAAAAUUUAAUAUGAUUUGUUGCUGAAUUGGCUCAUAGUAGGGAUGAAUUUUCUAUUGAAAUCAGGAUAAUUAUAGCUAUUAUGUAUUGAGUGCUAGCUAUGUGCUAGGCAUUGUGCCAAAUGCUUUUCUUGCUUUGUUUCAUUUUGUCCUCUCCCAAACCUUGUGAGACAUAGAUACUAUUUUUGUCUCUAUUUUACAGAUGAAAAUUCCUCUAAUCUCUUGCCCAAGGCCAGAGUGCUGGUGAGUGGCAGAGCCACCAUGUGGAUCCAAGUUUGUCUUAACUCUAAAGCCUGUAUUCUUUAACCACUUGGCAAUGCUAACUGUCCUCCUUCCAUCUUCUUAGUAGGGAUGAAUUUGCCAAUGGGACUAGAAAACAUGAUAUUUAUGGGCUUGGAUGUAGACACUGCUUGGUUGUGGACAUUACCAAAUACAUGUUUGCAACUCUCCUUAUUUUAUACCUCAGUGGUUGGUCAACCCCAUUCUUUCUUUGGGUAUAUUUCAAGCAGGUUACAAUCUGGUCUUUCAAGUCUGGGAUUUUAACGCUUAACUCUUAGUAGGCACUCUUAUUUCCCUUUUAUUCAAAUUCUUGAGGGAAGCUUCUUUAUAAACUCCUUAGACUGACAAAAAUAGUAAAAUCUCAGAAAUAGGCAAAUCAAGGGAGAUAAUGAAAUCACCAGAAUGGGCGUUUAACCGUGGAGUGUAAGGGAAGCUUUCCUGGAGAAAAUAGUUUAAUUUUGCAUUUGAAGGGUAGAUAAGAGCCACAAGAGGAAAGUUGGAAAAACCAUCUGGAAGAGGGAAUAGGAUUAGCAAAGGCACAAUUUCUUGAUGUUAGAGAUUUAAAUUUAAAAAAUAAAAUUAUGAAAAUGUUAAGAAAACAAUAGGUGACUCUGUAAUCCCACUGUUAUAAAAGAUUUUCAAAGCGUGAUAUCAAAGACAGAAGCCAUAAAGGGAAUGACAAAUACAUCUGAUUACAUAAAGAUUUAAAAAGCUUCCAUAAAUAAAAACCUAUCAUAAACAGAGCUGCAACAAUGACAGCCUGGGAAAAUUUUUUGCAAUAAAUUUCAGUCUAUAUUAGCUGUCAUUAAUAUAUAAAUAGCUCUUUACAACUCAGUUGAAAAGAACACACCAGCUGAAAAACAGUCAAAGUGCACAGAUGGUCACAUCCCAAAAGAAGAAAUAUGGCUGGCCAAUAUACCUGUUAGAAAAUAGUUUAACAUUUCUGGUAAUCUGAGGCAUGCAAAUUGUGUGUGUGUGUGUGUUUUGCCUGUUAAACACGUGAUAAUUACCAAAUGAUAAUGACCUGUUUGUCAGGUUGCAGCAGAAAACAGAUCCUUGUAUAUUGCUGGAGGGAAUAGCAAUUUAAAUAAUUUUUCUGGAGGGCAGUUUAGCAUUAUGGGUCAAAAGCCUUCAAAUGGAUAUUCCCUUUGAAGAUCUAGACUGUCUUCUAUCAAUGUGGGCUAAGGAAAUAGUAAAGGAACUGAAAAUUUAGAUGUAAUUUACAUGUGCAACCAGAGGAUAUUGGUUGAGUAAAUUAUUGCAUAUCCAUAUAAUUGAAUAAAAUGAAGGUAUUGGAAAAUGAGAUAGUAGAAGUGUAGUAAUUGACACAAAUACGUUCAGGGUACAGCUUGACAUAACGCGCAAGGCUGUCAUGCUGGAGAGGUAGGCAGGAUCUAGAGCAAAGAAGGCCUUGUCCGCCAUCCGAAGAACCUUGAGCUUUUUUGGUAGGUAGUGGCAAGCCAUGGAAGGAUUUAAAAUGGCAGAUCAGAGGGGCAUUUUAGAUAGAUCCCUCUUGUAGCAGUGUGCCUGGAGGCAGGAGACCAGUAAGGAAAUUAUUGCAGUGGUCCUGAAAGAGAUGAUGAGGGCCCAAGGGUAUGAAGUAGAUGGAGUCAUAGGACCAACUUUGGGCAGCCCAGAGAGUUAAUCUUCCUUAUGGUGGGUAACAGUCAUAAGCACUUGGCCUCAGCGAUCCCCAGAUAGCUAUGUGCCAUCCCAGGAGGUGCUGACAGGAGAACUGGAGCUUGGGGAGAUUGUGUGCUAGGCCAAACACCACUCUCCUGUACCUCUCUCACUCUGUUUCCCUUUCAUUUAGUUUGCCCAUAUCCCUUCAUUGCUUACCCUGGCUAGCCUCUCAUUUAGGAUGGCCUGUGGUCACUGGCCCUCCUUCCCAAUUACAUUUCUCAUAGUACUAACACUUGCUCCAGUGUACAAAAGCUAUCUUCUUUAAGUGCUAUGAAAAUGAGGAUUGUUGAAUGUAACACUGGGGUGGAGCAGAAGUGGAUGGGAGGCUGAACAAUGGUGGCAGUGAACUUGGGGCUGAUAUGACUGGGGGAACAGGAAUGGGAAGCAGGCCAGGUGUUGGCUGAGAGGUUCGGUAGAGAAGGUGGGAACCUGGAACCAGAGAGGUUCGCAGGUAGAGGAUGAACUGGGAUAACAGCUGAUGCCUAGAUUGGAUGCUUAGGAAAGAACUAAAGGUUAGUACAGGGAUCUUUCCUGAGGAAGCUGAGAGAGUGUGUGGUUUUGAAUGGAACCGUGGAUUUUUUCUGGGAAAACCAGCCAAAAAAGACCUCAGUUUUAUAAGGAUUGCAAGUGCCCACCAGACCUGGGGAUGAGGCAGGUGGGAGCUAUAAUGAACCUGUCUUUGGGACUCUGAAACUCAUCUAUGUAAAUGCAAUUUGCUGUCCAGUUGAGUUUGUGUUUUGAGAUGUCUCACACUGUAGAGAGUAGAUCUUAUGAGCUGGCUGAUGGCACAGGUGUGGGGCUGUUGGGGUGACUCCCUGUGUGCCAUGUGGUCAAGGGCCAGGGCUAGAGUCUAAAGAAAAGGAGCUCUCAUGAGCCCUGGUAUGUGUCAGGUGUGAAGUGGAAAGUGCAUUGAACUGGGAGUUAAGGGACCUGGGCUCUCAUCAGAAAGCUUGUCAGAACCUUUUCCCCUCAGUUUCCUCAUCUCUGAAAUGGGGUUUAAUAACAUGGUUCUGCCUGCCUCCCAGGUGAUGGGAAAGUGGAAGUGCUCUGUAGCACUUCUCUAUAUGCUACCUGCUCAUGCCUUUUGUUUCAGGUGCUGAGCUGGGCAGAUGUCAGCAUGAAUGCAAAGUGCCAAGUUGGUACUGGGGUAUGCUCAGAUAUAUUCUCAUCUUUGUACCAUCCUUGUUUGAACUUCUAAGUCUCAUCUCUUCCUAUUCUAUUUGCAGCCAAAGUGAUAGUUUAGCUUUUCACCUCCUAGUCUAAAAAUGCAUGCCACCAAAAUUUUCAGGCAGUUGGAAGCCAAGCAAAGAAGAAAGCAAGGAUAUUCAGACCAAGGCUGGGGGCCCUUGCACCUCUGAAUUAAAAUGUUAGUUCCAUGUGGCUCUGUUGGCUAAUGUUGAAUAUGAAUGUGACUCUAGCAUGACAGGGUGAAGAGGUUCAGUAUCAGAAAUCUGAGAAGUUGCUAAAGGAGGCCAUGAGUUUUCUGGAAAUGCAAUAUGAAUAAUCAGGAAUCCCCAGAUAACUGUGUACCAUCAUAGGAGGUGGAAUGUAAUGUAAUAAAUAAUCUUUCAAUCAGAUACAUUUAGUUAUAUCAAGUCAGCAGAUUUGAAAAAGGACCCUAGAGGCCAGGCACAGUGAUAAACCUGUAAUCCCAGCACUUUGGUAGGCUGAGGCAGGAGGAUUGCUUGAGGACAGGAGUUCGAGACCAGCCAGGGCAACAUAGUGAGACUCUGUCUCCACAAAAAAAUAAAAAUAAAAAUAAAAAAUAAAAAAAUUAGCCAGAUAUGGUGGUGCACACCUGUAGUCCCAGCUACUUGAGAGGCUGAGGUAGGAGAAUUGCUUCAGCCCAGGAGUUGGAGGGUACAGUGAGCUAUGAUUGCACCACUGCACUCCAGCCUGGAUAACAGAGUGAGACUUUCUCAAAAAAAAAAAAAAAAAAAAAAAAAGAUACCUUCUAUGCUGCUAUGCUGAUGAUAGAAAUAGGCAAGACAGAAAAGAUGAAACGACUAAAGUUAGAACCAUGACUGAUGGAGGAUAACAGGACAACCAACUGGGUUGAAACUGGAGGCUUGUUCUCUUUAAUAGUUUUCUGGGCUUCUAGCCUAGGGAAAUUGUGGAUCAGAACCAGCCAAAUGGACUUAUAAGGGAAAUUUGUCCCCGAAAAUCAGCUUACCUCCUCUUGUCUGUGGGUAUAGAAAAGUAAGAUUUAACUGUGGUGCCCAGUGUUGCAUUUUUACAUCUCUGUUUAGCAUGUUGGAAGUGUCUUGGGUAUUCCAGAAGCUCAGGAAGGCUGCUGGCAUGACUCUGGUGACUCCAGAAGUAUUGAGGACCUUUCUAAGGUGGUUGGGGCCCCUUCCUCUUCUCUGUGUACUGUAGCUUCUGAGUGUAGCCUUUGAUGGGCCUGAUGCUGGGUAACUAUGUGCAGCCUCCAACUUGGUCCCUUACCUAAGAUCUUUCUCCUGGCCUGCCCUCCAUGUCGGGGAGCUAUCGUCGUCUUCAAGCUACAGAUGCACAUGUUGAAUGGAGCUCUUCUGGCAUUGCUGUUUCCUGUGGUAAACACUCGGCUGCUCCCCUUUGAAUUGGAGAUUUACUACAUUCAGCAUGUUAUGCUCUACGUGGUACCCAUCUACCUGCUUUGGAAAGGAGGUGCUUACACUCCAGAGCCCCUCAGCAGUUUCCGGUGGGCUCUUCUCUCAACUGGCCUCAUGUUCUUUUAUCACUUCAGCGUCUUGCAGAUCCUCGGCCUGGUCACCGAAGUGAAUUUGAACAACAUGCUGUGUCCGGCCAUCUCAGACCCAUUCUACGGCCCCUGGUAUCGCAUCUGGGCCUCGGGACACCAGACUCUCAUGACCAUGACCCACGGGAAGCUGGUCAUCCUGUUCUCAUACAUGGCUGGGCCCUUGUGUAAAUAUCUGCUGGAUUUGCUCCGGCUUCCAGCCAAGAAAAUAGACUGAAGGUGCUUAUUUUUUUUUUUUUUCCUCCCUGAGGAAGCAAGUCGUGACUUGACUUGGAGAACACCCAGUUCUUGAUAAAAUCAUGGGAGAGGGCAGUAGGAUGUUUGGUGUAUUUCUUUUUCCUCCUUUCUGUCCCUUUCUUCUACCACUCUUCCUUUCCCAGCUCUUCCCCCUACGAUGUCUCCUUGAGCCUGGGGUGUAGUGCUGGGCGCUGGAUUUUCCUCCUUCCCUUUGGCUCUCUCUCUGCUCCUAGUGGCCUUACAUGGGGAGAUUGCAGUGAGCGGCUCUUUCACUCUGCUUGUCGGUGCUUUAACAACAGCUGGUUGAGGAGAAAGGGAACAACAAGUAGUAGUUCUUUUGGCAUCGAAGCAAUGAGAUUGGGUUGUGUUUCAUUUCUCCACUGCCAGGGACCUCCAGGCUUAUGCUGGCGUCCCAUUUAGUCUCCAGCACAGCCCUUACCACGGGGGACUGAGGCCUUGUUUCUAUACCAGCGGCAAGCCCAGAGCCGAGGGAUUUCACAGCUCGUGGUCAAGACAGAACCAGCCAGAUUCUGGUCACUGGUGUCCCAUGACUCAAAGUAAACAGCCAACCAGCCACUCCCUCCAGGAUGCUGCCUGGGGUGGGAGGUGAGAGCACCACCCAGCCCAAGGGCUAGAUUCCAUUGAGAGGGUUGGAGAUCUAUUGCAAUGACAAAUCCAAAGUGAAGAGGGUCAAGAUAUAUACAGUACUAGGCCAGACCCUGUGUAAGUUCUGCCUGUGAGAGUUGAGAACUGAUGCAUAUCCCAAUCAGAAGUGAGCACAGAAAACUGUGAUUUGAAUCAUACACUCUGUUUUAGGAAAAUGUUGAUAAUAGAUACCAUUUUAAUCUUGAGUGCCCCUUAAAUGUGUUCCCUCUCCCUUUCCCUCUCCCCCCACCCCUCCCCCUCCCCCCUCCCUCCCUCUUUCCCUCUCUCAGGCAGCUUCAGGGAAGAAUGAGCUGGAAUUGGCUGGUUGGUUGGUUUUUGAGUUUGGAGAAUCCUCGCAUCAGGGCCCAUUUCUGGAAGAUUCUGUAGAUCUGUUUCUUGGUUUUACAGGGCCAGUGUUGUUUCCCUAGGGCCAGAUUUCUUCAGUGUAUCCACACUCAGUGCUGAAUUGUUUAAUGUGGGGGACAUCACGUCCUCCUCAUCCUGUCUACCCCCAAAUCCCAUGUCUAGGUUGAAAGGGGGCUGCCAAAGAAUUAAGUCCUCAUGGGUGGAGGUUCAGGUGCUCCACAAGGAGGAGCUUUUGUUGAAGGACUUCAGCUCAGUUAUGCACGGACCUCAAGCAGGCAGGAAGUGGCUGGGCAUUGCUGACUCCACAUUGACUCCCACUAGGAACAGAUUUGCUUAAGAACAGAAAAGCUCAUUUGGUGAUUUUGUCUGAUGAGCCUCCCUUCCCCUGUCCCACUCUAGGCAACACAGUUGACCUAGACCAGUUCCAGUAUUUCCAGUUUGACCGUGUUUGACCUACACUGAGCUUCGGUGCCUCAGUGGUCAUAAUUUUAGCAAGUGGACCUAUAGGAAGCAACCCUGGGAGGGACCGUCCUUCUGCAGAGGCCUGCGGGCAUUGAGGCUAUCAAUCCCCAGGGCUUGGGGAGCAGGAGGGGAGGGCACCAAGUGCUCUUACUCUCCUGAGCUCCUUUUGAUGCGUAAGCUUUGUUUUUGGCCCUCUUUGAAGGCAGGGCCAAACUUUUCUUAGUGCCUCUCACCUUAGGGUGGCCCUCCAGGGAAGGUGCUCCUUGAAUGGCUGGAUUGGCCCUGCCCACCGUCAAACUGCUACAUGUAGGAAUAGCUGAUGAGGAAAUACACAAGGCCUCAGUGCCCCUUGGCCUCUUUACAAAAGGAGAAGUUGGAAGGGGAUUGUGGGAGGAGCCCCUGGGGGCCUGGUCUGUCCUCCACCAGAACUUGGAGUUGCUGCCAGCAGAGGAUCUGUGCCUCAGCUGAAGACUAGCUCCGGAAUGUCAUAGGGGUGUGACUGUGUAGGCCUUCUCCUCCUCCUCGUUUCUGUGGCAUGGCACAGGUUGCCUGGUUGCUCGAGCCUUCCCCAUGUUGACAUCCUCCACAAGCUUGCCUUUGCUCUGUCUACAGCUUAGUACCCCAUUCUGGAGGGCACUUUCUGGUGCUUGGAAGGAGAGAAGAAAGCAAAAGCCACAUGCCUGGCAUGGCCAAGCCAGAGACAGAUCCACCUGUCAGAGGAAGGAAGAAGUAAAGGGGGCAUGCAGGGCUUUUGGGGGCCAGAUUGGCUCAGAAACAUGUAGGUCAAAAGAAUAGAGGGGGCCCAGUCUAUAGGCUUCACAAGGAGCCAUGGCCUGUAUUUGGGGCAUUGGGGAGCAUAAGGCAUCUGAACUGGUCCAGAUCUCACUCUUAUCUUGGGCCAAGCCAACGUGGAGAGAAGCAACCCAACCAGACUCUUGGCAGCCUGCCUUACAGGGUAGCCCACCUUAUAGGGUAGCCCUCAUAUCUGCCCUGUGCCGGCCCUCUACUGCCCCAGCUUUGGUACAGGAGUGAGGGAGAAGCUGGAGCUUGCACACCCAGUGGCCAGUGGGGCUGUCUUCCCAGCUCCUCCUCAGGGCUUUCCUGUCAGUGCCAAGCCAGUUCCCCAGCCAGGUUUCCGUGUGCCAUUUGCCAGCGUGUGGGAGCUCUGCGCGUGUGUGAGGGUGUUUGUAGAAGAGGGCAGUUUCCUUUCAAAUGGCCUUAGGAAGGGAAAAGAGUACUCCCUCCAGCCCCUAGGUAGCCUUGGCCAGGGAUGUGGGCCAAGAACAGUCUGUGGAGCUGGCCAACUUGUGGCAUCCACUCCAAAUAGCAGAGACCCAGUCACGCCUGCUUCUGGUCCUCCCUGCCCUCAGUAUUUGGUUUUGUACACCAAAGAUGAUCUGGCCCAUCUUCCUCCCAGAGGCACAACAGUAACAUGUUCCUCUGUCAGCCUGUGAAGGCAUGCAGGGUUCUGAAGCCACAGACUCAGUCUCCCCAAGUCAGCAAUCUCUUUCUCUCUCUCUCCUCAAACUUCAUCGCAUUCAUAGAAGCUGCUUGCAGGGUCGCCGGGCUAACCAGGGUGAUCGGCGAACUUUACCGUACAGUACCUCAGUCUAGCUGUCAGAUCACCCCUUUUGCUGUAGCCUCUGUUGAGGUUUUUAUAUUUGUGAUCAUUGGUAAUUCAGUGUCCUAUGAAGUGGGCACAGCUCCCCACAGAGAGCAAGUUGUCAGCAGGUCUCUGUGCACUGGUAUUGGGGCAGGGCAGUGCCCUGGGGGUAAGCUAGGUGGCUCAGGGAGUGGCAGAAGGGCCAUUUUUCCCUCUGCCAAAAAGACUUCCUUGGAUUUGUAGAUGUUGACCCAGAGUCCUCUGUCCCCUCCUGAAGAGGAUUUUCUUACUGGUUUCUACUGAAGGGGAGGUAGGGGAGGAGGAAAAAAGGACCAUGUGUGAUGCUGUUAGACAAGACACUGACGCUGAUUAUGGAGGGUCUCCUGCAGGCCCUUGUGGGCUCCUUGGCAAGGCCCCAGGCUGGGAAGGAGCUCCCCCCACUGCCCAUCCUGCCCGCUUUGUGGCGGGUAGAGUCAGUGACAGGGAGGCAGCCCUCCUUUUGUGUAUAUAGAGUGAGCUGAUUUGGGCUCAGGAAAACCUAGUCGCUUGUUGCUCUCGUCUGUGACAUUUUUGUACACUGGUUUGCUACUCAUGGCAAGAAACAGACAAAGCCCCAUGAAAAAUAAAACAAAACAAAAGUCAUUUCAAACAAAGCUGUUGUUUUGAAAACUCUUGCUUUCUUUUGGUGUCCAUUUUGUGUUCUAUUUUAAAGAAUCUUUCAUUUAUAUUGGUGUUAUUGUAGUGAAGAGAAUGUGAUAGGCUGAUCUGUAAUGGUUUCUGUCAGGAGCUUAGCAAAUGCCUCUGCCCCUCUUCCCCUACCCCUGUCCUUCCUCAGUUCCCAGCUGGGAUUGCUAUGCACUGGGCAGACCCGUCACUGUCUCCCCUGAACCCCCACACAGUGGCUUCCCUUAGAACCAGUCUUUGUACUCUCCCUAAACAGCAGCAGGCUUAGGAUUUUUGUCAGGCUGGUUCUUGCGUGCUCUGUGCCCCCACCAGUUUGCUCACCUCUUGGGGCAUUUUGUAAUGUGUUUUCUCUGUCUUGUAAAACCUUUUGAUUGUACCGAAAUGGUAUCUGCAGUCGCCUUUGGAAAUAAAUGGUCAUUAAUUUGUGUACUUAGCAUUCUGAAUUUUAGUCUCAGGUGUUUCUGUUGUUGAAGAUCCUUGAAUGAAAAGGAACCCUCACCAUGGGGCUUACUGUUAUAAUGUUUCUUCAUUUACUGUUAUUAAAAGAUUUAUGAGAA